AGAUGCCCAUCCUCUGCCAUCUAAGAACUUCAACAUAAUCUCUCUUAGAACAUAAAUUUUCAGAAAUUUUCUGUCUCUCAAAGUAUUUUCUUCCAAUUCAAUAACUGCUAUGGGCUUUGUUUUUAUUUUUUAUUACCUAUGUGAAGUUCUCUGUCUCUCAGGAACUAUGAUUUGAUUCUGGAUUGGAUUCUUAGAAUGGAAAAUAAUAUGCUCUUUUUUCUGGUUAAGUUCCAUAAGUUUGGAUACUUCUAUUAAGAGAAAGGUAAAAUGUGGAUGGAAGCCAAUAGAAAACAUGUUAAAGUAUAUACUACUCAAAGAUUCACGUGGCACAUCUCAUCUUUGAUUUACCUCUUAGGAACAACAAGGUAAACAGUAUACUAUAGUCAUUCAGGUUGUCAAAGGUAUGAGCAACAUAUGUUUUUAAAGUCACUGAUUUUAUCAUUCUAUAAAUGUGGAUCAUGAAAUGAAUCAACUGUGAAAAUCUGGAAGAAAAUGCAGUACUUGCCAAAGACCACAGGUUUUCCGAAGGUCAACAAUGAAAAACAGAACCAUGUUUGGUGAGUUUAUUCUACUGGGCCUUACAAAUCAACCUGAACUCCAAGUGAUGAUAUUCAUCUUUCUGUUCCUCACCUACAUGCUAAGUAUCCUAGGAAAUCUGACUAUUAUCACCCUCACCUUACUAGACCCCCACCUCCAGACCCCCAUGUAUUUCUUCCUCCGGAAUUUCUCCUUCUUAGAAAUUUCCUUCACAUCCAUUUUUAUUCCCAGAUUUCUGACCAGCAUGACAACAGGAAAUAAAGUUAUCAGCUUUGCUGGCUGCUUGACUCAGUAUUUUUUUGCUAUAUUUCUUGGAGCUACCGAGUUUUACCUCCUGGCCUCCAUGUCUUAUGAUCGUUAUGUGGCCAUCUGCAAACCCUUGCAUUACCUGACUAUUAUGAGCAGCAGAGUCUGCAUACAACUAGUGUUCUGCUCCUGGUUGGGGGGAUUCCUAGCAAUCUUACCACCAAUCAUCCUGAUGACCCAGGUAGAUUUCUGUGUCUCCAACAUUCUGAAUCACUAUUACUGUGACUAUGGGCCUCUCGUGGAGCUUGCCUGCUCAGACACAAGCCUCUUAGAACUGAUGGUCAUCCUCUUGGCCGUUGUGACUCUCAUGGUUACUCUGGUGCUGGUGACACUUUCUUACACAUACAUUAUCAGGACUAUUCUGAGGAUCCCUUCUGCCCAGCAAAGGACAAAGGCCUUUUCCACUUGUUCCUCCCACAUGAUUGUCAUCUCCCUCUCUUAUGGCAGCUGCAUGUUUAUGUACAUUAAUCCUUCUGCAAAAGAAGGAGGUGCUUUCAACAAAGGAAUAGCUGUACUCAUUACUUCGGUUACUCCCUUACUGAAUCCCUUCAUAUAUACUUUAAGAAAUCAGCAAGUGAAACAAGCUUUCAAGGACUCAGUCAAAAAGAUUGUGAAACUUUAAAAAAGGAGAUUACACUUCAAAAUACAUUUUCACUUAACAAAUAUGCAUUGAAUGUCUAUAUUUCAAGUGCUAAAUUGGCCCUUGAAGAUUAAAAUAGGAAAAGUAUAUGUCUUAAUUUCAAGAAAACUAUAGUCUAGAAUCAAGGAAAGAUAUAUAAAUGGUAAAUUUAUGUAAUAAAUUUACAAAAAACAAAAUAAUAUUUUAAUUGUUAUUAGAGAAGAGUGAAUGGGGAUCUGAAAAGGAACAGUUGGAAAGAAUUAGUUCUGUUUUCCAUAAAUUAUUUGAAAUUUAAGAAGCAAAACAGAUUGUUUAUUUAGAAGAGUAGGAGGAUAAGAAUUUAGAGUGAAAAAGGAAACCAGAUCAUAAAAGUAAGUAAUUACAACUACUGAGUUAGCUGGGUUUCAUGAGUCAAGAAAUUUUCAGAAUUGUUUUGAGGAGAAUGUAGUAUCAGCAUUGUUCUUCAGCAUGGAGCCCUGGAGACUAUGUUUCCAUCGAGGAGUGAAUAAUUUUUCUUCUCCUCCAUUUUUUCAUCUAUAUUUCAAAUGUAACCAUUGCAACUUCCCUCCUUUCAUAAGAGGAAAAUGAAAGAAUAUAUAUUUAGUCUACUUUUCUCCAAAUGAGGAGAAAAUUUUUAAGAUUUUUGUCAACUUAAUAUGUCCAUUUUCUAGUUUAUGGUUAAAACAGGUUUCUAGAGACAAGUUUAGAAGGCUUUCAUUCUCCUAGACAAAAUCUAUUGUUUCUUUUCUUAGGUGACAUUUUAAGUUAAUGGCAUGAGAUCUGUUUUCUCUCUCUUUGAUAGUUUCUGGUAAUUUUUUCCUUCCUAUCAUGAUUUUAUUUUCAUCCUUUUGUUUCACUUUAUUAGAUAUUAGAAAAGAAAAUUCUGUUAUCUGGCUCUACUUCUUUAACUUUCCCCCAGAUUUUUGCUUUCGUUUGUAACAUAAACCAUGGAUGACCAUUUUAUAAAGUAAAAAGAAUAUAAAGUGUCAAUGCAAUCUUAUAUCUAGAAUGUUCCAAAUUAUGAGUCUUGAAAAACAACUAGAAAUAGACUAUCCUACCAAAAACUUUACACAUGGAUUCAAGGCAAUGACAACUUGAAUUUGAAUAGGUAGUGGUAGUGUCCAAUUUCAAUGGAAGUAAGCACUUUUUUUUAAUCUGAGCAUUUGUACACAGUUUAAUAAUAUCUUAAAAAAUUGCAGGAGCUUUGUUACUAUUUGGGGUAAAAGUGGAACACAAUCUGGUAUUUUCACAUGCUUUAUAUGUGGUAAUAUGUUGAGUAAAAUGAGGUACUUCUCAAGCAUUUAAGGAACAAGCUGGAUUGAACUGAUUAUGAGAGCAAAUUAUCAGAGCCACAGAAGGUAUUGGAGAAUGUAUAAUAUUUUUGAAAAAGUAUUUUAUGUAAAGCUGUUGCUAUUCUGAGUAUCUUGUUUUCUUUGGUUGCUAGCUAGAGAUUAGUGAUAAUAUUCAAUAUAUUCCAAAUUUAAUGCACUACAAGAACAAGAAGUGUUCUUGAAUAGCCACAUCUAAAUCAUUAAGUUCCCCUACACCCACAUUUCUACUAAAACCUAUGGUACAGUGGGAGCAAUGUCAUAUAGUGGCUUAAAACAUAGGCUUUAGUUCAAAUCCCAGAUUUUCAACUUUCUACCAAAGUUACCUGGGGAUAGUUACUUGAUCUCUCUAAGGCUCACCUCUGUCAACUCUAAAAUGUUUACAAUAAUAGUGUCUAUCUUAUAGUUUUGAGCAUUCACUGAGAAAAUAGAUGUAAAAUAUUAAAAGACAGCCAGUAUUUAUUGUGUUUAAUAAAUGACAUCUAUUAUAACUAUAUUAUAAACAAUAUAUUUUUCAAGGAACUGGAGCUUAACUAGAAAGAAGGCAUUAAAUUGGUUGGUUUAAUAUAGCAGGGACAGUAAAAAUGUUGGCCAUUGUACUUGAAAUCCAUCUGCACAAGGCCAGCAUAUUUCUACUCUCCACACAUCCAGCUGCAUGCUGGGUAGCUGGGUCAGCAAAGAUCUUACCUACUCUUCAGAUAAAGCCAUCAAAAUACUUGGCAGCAGGUUAUAAGAACUGGGCUAGCAUCAACUUCAUUGCCCUAGAUAUCUAUGGGAGAGACAGGAUGUAUUAACAUGCUGAGACAAGGAAGGAAGGUACUUUGUGUAAGUUAAUGUUUAAGAUCACUAGGCAAGAGUUCACUCAGCAUUCUUUAUAUAAGCAUUUGGAAAUGAACAUGGAAAAGAAUGUAUCACCUUCUAAAUGAGCUUGUCAAAAAAAAAAAAGCAAGUCAUAUUCUUCUAAAGCUGUUCAUCUAGUCUGGCUGUAUGUUAAUUCAUACUUGGAAUGUAAUCCAAGUCAUAGAUAAGCAAAAGGAAUGACUUCACAGAGUCUGGUGCUGAGCUACCAGAAUAUUCAGUAUCUAAAUAUAUAAAAUGGUGAGUUUGAUUCCUCAUGUCACCAAAGUGGACAAGAAUUAAAAGAAACAGCUUUAGCUGCCUAACAUUCUCAGAAUCAUAUUAUACCAGUGCUAGGGUGAGGAGACUAUGAAAAUGAGUAAAAGCCAAUCUGCUACAUUUGGGCAUUCAUUCUUCUAUUGCCUCUCUUUAAAGCUGCCAGAGCUUGUGGAUAUAUGGAUUACAAUUCUAAACAGGUAGUCUUCCAGCAUCAUUUCUUGCAAAGAGUUUUAAAUAAAAUUCAAAACAAUAAAAUAUAUUUUUUAAUUUUUUUUAUUUCAGCCAGGAUCAGUGACUCACACUUCUAAUCCCAGCUCUUUGGGAGGCUGAGGCAGGCGGAUCACUUGAGGUCAGGAGUUCAAGAACAGCCUGGCCAACACAGUGAAACCCCGUUUCUACUAUUACAUUGAUAGAAAAGUAAUUGUGGUUUUUGCUACUAAAAGUAAUGGCAAAAACUGCAAUUACUUUUGCACCAACCAAAUAAAAAUACAAAAAUCAGCCAGGCAUGGUGAUGCGUGCCUGUAAUUCCAGCUACUGGGAAGGCUGAAGCACAAGAAUCACUUGGAGUACAAGUGGCCUUUUGUUACAUCAGUGAAUUAAAUAGUGGUGAAUUCUGGGAUUUUAGUGCACCUGUCACCCAAGUAGUAUACAUUGGACCUAAGCUGUAGUUUUUUUAUCCCUAGCCCCCUCCCAUCAUUCCCCUUCUGAGUCUCUAAAGUUCAUUAUACCACUCUGUGUGCCUUUGCAUACUCAUAGCUUAGCUCCCACUUACGAGUGAGAACAUACUUAUAAGUGAGAACAUAGUUUUUGGUUUUCCACUCCCGUAUUACUUCACUUAGAAUAACGACUUCCAGCUCCAUCCAAACUGCUGCAAAAUACAUUCUUUUGUUCCUUUCCAGGCCAGGUGCAGUGGCUCUUGCCUGUAAUCCCAGAAAUUUGGGAGGCUGAGGAGGGUGGAUCACUUGAGUUCAGGAGUUCGAGACCAGCCUGGCCAACAUGGUGAAACCCUGUCUCUAUCAAAAAUACAAAAAUUAGCCUGGUGUGGUGGCACGUGCCUGUAGUUCCAGCUACUUGGGAGGCUAAGGUACAAGAAUCACUUGAACCAGGGAGGCAGAGGUUGUAGUGAGCUGAGUUUAUGCCACUGUACUCCAGGCUGGGCAACACAGCAAGACUCUGUCUCAAAAAAACAUAAAAUAAAAUAAUAAAAAAUGUUGCUUCUUUUCAUGGCUGAGUAG